AUCCUAUGACGCGAAAGUAACCGAGACUAUCAGGAUCCGGAGACGGAAAUGUCCGAAGGCCGCAGUACUUGACCCUGUAUUUUGGGAGUCGAACGGAGACUCUGCCAUCGUCCUCAAAGAGUAAAAAAUCCAGUUACGGAAGGGAACUAACACUUGCUAGAUAUGGUGUGCAGAGUGCGUUUGCAAAGAAACUUAAGAGAAAACAAAUGAUAGGACACAGGGUGGUGGAAGAUCUCAAAGAUCAAGCACCACAUACCGACAGACCGCAUGUAUGACAGUGGUCCCAUAAGAUUAUAGGAAUGGAAACUGAAAGUGGAAAUCAGGAAAAGGUAAUGGAAGAAGAAAGCACUGAAAAGAAAAAAGAAGUUGAAAAAAAGAAACGGUCACGAGUUAAACAGGUGCUUGCAGAUAUUGCUAAGCAAGUGGACUUCUGGUUUGGGGAUGCAAAUCUUCACAAGGAUAGAUUUCUUCGAGAACAGAUAGAAAAAUCUAGAGAUGGAUAUGUUGAUAUAUCACUACUUGUGUCUUUUAACAAAAUGAAAAAAUUGACUACUGAUGGGAAGUUAAUUGCCAGAGCAUUGAGAAGUUCAGCUGUUGUAGAGCUUGAUUUGGAAGGCACCAGAAUCCGGAGGAAAAAACCUCUGGGGGAAAGACCAAAGGAUGAGGAUGAACGCACAGUGUAUGUGGAGUUACUUCCCAAAAAUGUUAAUCACAGCUGGAUUGAAAGAGUAUUUGGGAAAUGUGGCAAUGUUGUUUAUAUAAGUAUACCACAUUAUAAGUCUACUGGAGAUCCAAAGGGAUUUGCGUUUGUGGAAUUUGAAACAAAAGAACAAGCAGCAAAAGCAAUUGAGUUUCUUAACAACCCACCAGAAGAAGCACCAAGAAAACCUGGCAUAUUUCCUAAAACAGUGAAAAAUAAGCCCAUUCCAGCCUUAAGAGUUGUGGAAGAGAAGAAAAAGAAAAAGAAGAAGAAAGGCCGAAUGAAAAAGGAAGACAAUAUCCAAGCCAAAGAAGAAAACAUGGACACAAGCAACACCAGCAUCAGUAAAAUGAAAAGAUCCAGACCCACAUCUGAGGGCUCUGACAUUGAGUCCACUGAACCCCAAAAGCAGUGCUCAAAGAAAAAGAAAAAACGGGACAGAGUUGAAGCAUCUAGCUUACCUGAAGUCAGAACAGGGAAGAGGAAGAGAAGCAGCUCUGAAGAUGCAGAAUCCCUAGCUCCCCGAUCAAAAGUAAAGAAAAUUAUUCAGAAAGACAUCAUUAAGGAAGCAUCAGAAGCUUCCAAGGAAAAUAGAGCCCCAUGUCUUAACGGAGAGCUUUUUUAUUUAUUUCAAGAUAUAGAAAUCUCUACUGAAGAGGAAAAGGAUACUGGAGAUCUAAAAGAUAGCUCUCUCUUGAAAACAAAAAGGAAACAUAAGAAAAAACAUAAAGAGAGACAUAAAAUGGGAGAAGAAGUUAUACCAUUAAGAGUGCUAUCAAAGAGCGAAUGGAUGGAUUUGAAAAAAGAGUAUUUAGCGCUACAAAAAGCUAGCAUGGCUUCUUUAAAAAAAACAAUAUCCCAAAUAAAAUCAGAGUCAGAAAUGGAAACAGACAGUGGAGUACCUCAAAACACUGGAAUGAAAAAUGAAAAAACAGCCAACAGGGAAGAGUGUCGCACCCAGGAGAAAGUUAAUGCAACAGGACCACAGUUCGUGAGUGGAGUGAUUGUGAAGAUCAUUAGCACAGAGCCUCUACCUGGCAGGAAACAAGUCCGGGAUACUUUGGCAGCAAUCUCAGAAGUUCUUUAUGUUGAUUUGCUAGAAGGGGAUACAGAAUGCCAUGCUAGAUUUAAAACUCCUGAGGAUGCUCAAGCAGUAAUAAAUGCCUAUACAGAAAUUAACAAGAAACACUGCUGGAAACUCGAGAUCCUUUCUGGUGAUCACGAACAAAGGUAUUGGCAGAAGAUUUUGGUUGAUAGACAGGCAAAACUUAAUCAGCCUCGGGAAAAGAAAAGAGGCACUGAAAAGUUAAUCACCAAAGCUGAAAAGAUUAGACUGGCAAAGACUCAACAAGCGAGUAAACAUAUAAGAUUUUCUGAAUAUGAUUGAAAAAAAAAACAGUUCACCUCUUAAUACUUCACAAGAUACUUGAGCUGUUCUUGGGAGAUUCACUUUUAUUAUGGUAGCACUGCAUAAUUAAUGUGUUUUUAAUUAAAAGAAAUAUCUUUGUUCCUCAACUUGUAAAUAAGACUUUUUUCUAGAGACAAAUAUGAUGUAUACCACAAUUUUUCUUAAACAUUUUAUUUGUUGAAAUUAUCUUAGAUGUCAGUGUCAGGUGAUUUAGUAAAUAAAUGUGUUUUGAACAUUA